GACGGCGCCCGCGACGACGACAAGGAUGGGGCCCAUCUCUUCGGAGCCUAAGGAUCCAGCCCAGGUCCAGCCCUGCGCAGCCGCCCACCAAGCUGCCAGAAGACGAGCCGGACGCCCAAGGCUACGAGAGGACGAUUGCAGAAUUGUACAGGCUAGUGGUUGGGGAAUAUUUUUUCGUGGAAGGGACCGUCUUCCUUAGCUGUGGCCCUCUCAUCAGGUCUGGGAAGAGGUAAUUGGAAAAUAGAACUCAUGGAGAAGUGUUACCACAGGCCAUGGACAAGGCCAGAAUUUCCCUGACAUCUGUCCGCCAGCACCGCCCUUCAGGUACAAUUCCACAAGAGACCCCCCAAACUUGAUGAAGUCACCCGCUUACAAGGGCUCACUCUCCACCUGCGCAAGGACUGCAAUUCCCAGGGGCCUCCAGGGCACCCGGCCGCUCCAGUCCAGUCGUGCAGGCGGCGCGCUCUUUCUCGCUCCGCUCAAGUCCAGGAACCGGUUCCCGGGCUCCCAGCCUCUCGGCAGCGCCCACGCGCCUGGGCCAAAGUCCGCGAACGGAAGCCGGCGGCGAGGAGGAUUCUGGGAGUUGGAGGCCGAGGCUGCGACCUGCGCAGGCGCAAACCUGCCCCUGGGGUGAGGGCUGUAAGUGGCGCGAUUCGCGGCAGCGCCCCGAUGGAACCUCCUGGUCCUGUGAGCUGCAAGAUAGAAAGCAACAUAUGCCCCCAGGUGGCCUCCCUCACCCUGGCAAUGGAAACGAACAGCCGAGCUUCACCGGACAAGACUAGAAAUCGUUCCUCCACCCACCCAGAGACAAAGCAUAUUUGACUUCUUCCUCUACUGGGGCCCUUGCAAGAUUCCAGCUGGUAUGAGCCUUCUGCAGAGCUAGUGCAGACUAGGAUGGCUGUAUCACUAACAGCAGCUGAAACUCUGGCCCUUCAGGGUACACAGGGACAAGAGAAGAUGAUGAUGAUGGGACCAAAGGAAGAGGAACAGUCUUGUGAGUAUGAGACCAGGCUACCUGGGAACCACUCUACCAGUCAAGAGAUCUUCCGCCAACGCUUCAGGCAUCUCCGCUACCAGGAGACUCCUGGUCCCCGGGAGGCCUUGAGCCAACUACGAGUACUCUGCUGUGAGUGGCUGAGGCCAGAGAAACACACGAAGGAGCAGAUCCUGGAGUUCCUGGUGCUGGAACAAUUCUUGACCAUCCUGCCUGAGGAGCUCCAAUCCUGGGUGCGGGGACAUCACCCUAAGAGUGGAGAGGAGGCUGUGACUGUGCUGGAGGAUUUAGAGAAAGGACUUGAACCAGAGCCGCAGGUCCCAGGCCCUGCACAUGGACCUGCACAGGAAGAGCCAUGGGAGAAGAAGGAAUCUCUGGGAGCAGCCCAGGAAGCACUGAGCAUCCAGCUCCAGCCUAAGGAGACCCAGCCUUUCCCAAAGAGUGAACAGGUAUAUUUACAUUUUCUGUCAGUUGUUACAGAAGAUGGCCCAGAGCCCAAGGACAAAGGAUCAUUGCCACAACCACCCAUUACUGAAGUGGAAUCACAGGUGUUCUCAGAAAAACUUGCUACUGACACCUCUACAUUUGAAGCUACCUCUGAGGGUACCUUAGAACUGCAGCAGAGAAAUCCCAAAGCGGAGAGACUGAGGUGGUCCCCUGCCCAGGAGGAAAGUUUCAGGCAGAUGGUUGUCAUCCAUAAGGAAAUUCCCACAGGGAAGAAAGACCAUGAAUGUAGUGAAUGUGGUAAAACCUUCAUUUAUAACUCACAUCUUGUUGUCCACCAGAGAGUUCAUUCUGGAGAGAAACCCUAUAAGUGUAGUGACUGUGGGAAAACUUUCAAACAGAGCUCAAACCUCGGUCAGCAUCAGAGAAUUCAUACAGGAGAGAAACCCUUCGAAUGUAAUGAAUGUGGGAAGGCCUUCAGAUGGGGUGCUCAUCUUGUUCAGCAUCAGAGGAUUCACUCAGGAGAGAAGCCCUAUGAGUGUAAUGAGUGUGGGAAGGCCUUUAGUCAAAGCUCAUAUCUAAGUCAGCAUCGGAGAAUUCACAGUGGAGAGAAACCUUUUAUAUGUAAAGAAUGUGGGAAAGCUUAUGGAUGGUGCUCAGAGCUCAUUAGACAUCGGAGAGUUCAUGCCAGAAAAGAGCCUUCCCAUUGAAUUGAAGGGGAGAACGUCUCCAGACAGAAUUCUACAUCGGUCUAAUCUACUUUAGGACUGGAUCCCAUAAAAGUUAUAAGUUCCUUAA